AGCUGGAGCUACCGAGCGGUGCCAGGCCAGGUGUGUGCGUCCGUCGGUCUUUCCGUGCCCACGCCGGAGACCAGCCCCGGAGGCCGCCUGGGCCUAUCCCUGUGCCAGGCACCAUGAAGCAGGAGUCUGCAGCCCCGAACACCCCGCCCACCUCGCAGUCCCCUACGCCGUCCGCUCAGUUCCCCCGAAACGACGGCGACCCUCAAGCGCUGUGGAUUUUCGGGUACGGCUCCCUGGUGUGGAGGCCCGACUUCGCCUACAGCGACAGCCGUGUGGGCUUCGUGCGCGGCUACAGCCGCCGUUUCUGGCAGGGAGACACCUUCCAUCGGGGCAGCGACAAGAUGCCUGGCCGUGUGGUGACGCUCCUUGAAGAUCAUGAGGGCUGCACUUGGGGCGUGGCAUACCAAGUGCAAGGGGAGCAGGUAAGCAAGGCCCUGAAGUACCUGAAUGUGCGAGAGGCAGUGCUUGGUGGCUACGAUACCAAGGAGGUCACCUUCUAUCCCCAAGAUGCUCCUGACCAACCACUGAAGGCAUUGGCCUAUGUGGCCACCCCACAGAACCCUGGUUACCUGGGCCCUGCGCCUGAAGAGGCCAUUGCCACGCAGAUCCUGGCCUGCCGGGGCUUCUCCGGCCACAACCUUGAAUACUUGCUGCGUCUGGCAGACUUCAUGCAGCUCUGUGGGCCUCAGGCGCAGGACGAGCACCUGGCAGCCAUCGUGGACGCUGUGGGCACCAUGUUGCCCUGCUUCUGCCCCACCGAGCAGGCUCUGGCGCUGGUGUGAGGGGCUGAGCCCCUGCGGGGAGUGCUCAUGUGGACAUCAGGGCCAGACACCCACUCCAGUGCACAAGACAGACUUGCGACCGCUUGAGCCCACUGAGCAGAUAUGGUGGGUGGCUGGAGGCUUCUCUUUCUCAGUCCCUGCCUGUCUGCCAGCCUGCAGCUCUCCUGCUUGACACUGACUUACUACUUGAAACUUUAUUUAUUGCACCAUGUUGGUGUGGUGGGCAGGUGGAGGGCCUGCCCUGGACACAGGGGCCCUGCUGAGCAGUGGCCCCAUCCUGGAACUUGACCAGAUUCCCCCCAGUGCUGCUGCUAACCCCACACCACCCAGGCCUCCACCUCCCCAGGGAGUCUCCAAGAGCCUCGAUCCUCUGCUCACUCAGCCCAGCCAUCCAUAGCCCUGGGAAUUCCACCUGCCAAGGAUCCCAGCAGGCUGGAUGAGGGAUAGUAGGGCAUGAGGAGAAGGAGCCCUGUAAGGACUGAGGCCCCGGCCAGCCCUUCUCCUCCACCAGUUCCCCAGAGCAGAGCUGGAGCUGAUGCCUGGACACAGCUGCUGAGCCUGGCCUGGGCCUCUUACCCACUUGGUUGUUUUCUUGUCCCUCUGUCUGUCUGUCUAUCUACUUGUCUGUCUGGGCCACUCCUGCCUGUGUGUUGGUCUAUUCCUGGGAAGCUCAUCACUACAGGCCCUGGCAACCUUCCCAGUCUGUCCCAUACUGUUACCCAUAAAACUAUCUCUUUA